CUCUUCCAGGGCGGGCGGUGUGGUGCACGCAUUGCUGUGCUCCAACUCCCUCAGGGCCUGUGUUGCCGCACUCUGCUGCUAUGAGCUUCCUCAAAAGUUUCCCGCCGCCUGGGCCAGCGGAGGGGCUCCUGCGGCAGCAGCCAGACACUGAGGCUGUGCUGAACGGGAAGGGCCUCGGCACUGGUACCCUUUACAUCGCUGAGAGCCGCCUGUCUUGGUUAGAUGGCUCUGGAUUAGGAUUCUCACUGGAAUACCCCACCAUUAGUUUACAUGCAUUAUCCAGGGACCGAAGUGACUGUCUAGGAGAGCAUUUGUAUGUUAUGGUGAAUGCCAAAUUUGAAGAAGAAUCAAAAGAACCUGUUGCUGAUGAAGAAGAGGAAGACAGUGAUGAUGAUGUUGAACCUAUUACUGAAUUUAGAUUUGUGCCUAGUGAUAAAUCAGCGUUGGAGGCAAUGUUCACUGCAAUGUGCGAAUGCCAGGCCUUGCAUCCAGAUCCUGAGGAUGAGGAUUCAGAUGACUACGAUGGAGAAGAAUAUGAUGUGGAAGCACAUGAACAAGGACAGGGGGACAUCCCUACAUUUUACACCUAUGAAGAAGGAUUAUCCCAUCUAACAGCAGAAGGCCAAGCCACACUGGAGAGAUUAGAAGGAAUGCUUUCUCAGUCUGUGAGCAGCCAGUAUAAUAUGGCUGGGGUCAGGACAGAAGAUUCAAUAAGAGAUUAUGAAGAUGGGAUGGAGGUGGAUACCACACCAACAGUUGCUGGACAGUUUGAGGAUGCAGAUGUUGAUCACUGAAAAUGAUUUAUGCAAGUUUAAGAUUCUGCUCCUAAGUGUAGGAGAGAACUUGGUGCCUCUUCCACUCUGGAGUGAAGUUAAUGAAAGUCUUUUUCCUUUUCCAAAACCCAACCUGAACCAGUUCUUUCUUGAGACAGACUAUACUGAGACAACAAGUUGUCACCAGCAGAAGAUAGAUAAUAUGACCUUUAUUAACUUGAUGAAUUAACUUAACCAAGAGGGUAUUUGUAGUUUACUAUUUACCCUAAAACUUUCUGUGUCUGGGUACCCUCUGAGUAGGCCUAUAAUUCCUACCUUGACUGUGUGCAUCAUUUGUAAGCUAGCAGAUCUAUGUGGUGAAAAUGCACAGGAGCUUGGUAGACUGCGGGGGAAAGAGAGAGCUCCUUUCGCCAUGUUUUACCAGUCUGCUGUUAUAACCUCUUAGGUUGUAUCCUUUAAUUUCCAGCCUUUUAGGUUAGUUUCUGUAACAGAACAAGUGAGUCUGGGAUGAAGUCCUCAAAGUACUUCAAAUGGUAAUUGUUUUGUUUUUGUAAUAGCUUAACAAAUAAACCUAGGUUUUCUAUAUUACUUUGCUCUCAUUCUUGACUAAAACCAUUAAUGAGAAAUGUUUUUUAAAAAAUAAUGCUGGCAAAUAUGAGAAUUUUGUUGGCUUUAUUUUUGUUUACUUGUUGAGAAGAUGAACAUGAAAUUAAUAAGAAAAUAUAGUUAUAGCUUCUGGCAAGUAUUUAGUAAGGCAAAGAUUUAACACAUUUCAGGGGAUUUCUGCCACUUCCUUUUAGAUCAGCAGUAAUUUCUUAUAUUUAUCAACUCUCAAUUUUUAGUUUUCAUAGAUACCUGGGUAUUAUAAGGCUGAUUUGUAAUUACUGAUUUAUACUUGGACUUUUGAAAUCAUUAUGUGUCCUUAAAAAUAAGGUUAUACAAGCUAACCUUCUUAACAGGAUCACAUGGCUAAUUAGUGACUAAACUGAUGUUUGGUACCACUCAGCCCAGUGUUCAUUUCAGCACUGUCACUUGGUUUCCCUUAUCUUGCAAGGUAGACUGAAAAAAAACGAAUUUUCCUUUUUCUAACCAGACUCUCAGAAUUUCUGAGUCUGUUAACAAUAGGCAAGUAAAACAGCCACUUGAAAUGGAAACUAAAAUUUACUGAGACCUCUGUACUAGCCACUGUCCUGAGUUCUUUAUUAUGUAUUAUAAUAUUCUUAAUUAUCUUAUGAGAUACGCUUUUAUCCCACUUUAUAGUUGAGGAAACUGAGUUAUAGAGAGAGGUAAAAUAACUUGCUUAAGGUCAUGUAGAUAGUGAAUUGUGAUUUUUGAGCCUGUGCUUUAAAACAUCAUACAGCCUUACCACCUACCAGCAGCAGAAAGCAUGCACACUCUCCCCACUGCUGCAGGGUUUCAGUGUUAACAUUUCAAUGGCCAGUACAAGAGCUUCCCCAGUUUCUCUGCUACCCAUCUGAGCAACACCCAUAAUUCUAUCCUAGAAGUUUGUCCAUUCUUCAGUAAUCAGUCAGGACAUUCUCACAGGCUAAUAUUAGAAAUUCCAUUUGAGUUCCUUUUAAAAGGAACAAAUUUAUAAUUGUGACUUUCCAUGAACAUAAAUUGCUCUGAUAGCAAAAUGUCGAGAAGAUUCAGAGUGUACUUGGUUUCUUGUUGGUGUUGCUGUGGUCAAUGCAAUAUGCAAAAAGGCAGGAGACCAAAGCAUGUGGGCACCUCUCUGGGCUUAUUUCCUCAUUAGACUAAGUGACUUUCAAAGAUUGAGCUGUAACAUUCACUAGAUAGUUAGAACCGUAGCAUUGAGAAAAUAGAAGCUGAGAAAAAAGAGCAGGUCAGGCUUUUAAAAGAUAAAAUUUAUAAUGAUCAGCCAGACAAUAUUUAUUGAUUUCAUUUGAGCCUAAUUUUAGGGUUGCUGGAAUUGUUUUCUUUGUGUGUUCCUGAUGUAGAGACACUUUAAAGGUACAUAGACAUUUCCCCUCCAAAAUGUAAGUCAUCUAAAUGUUCCUAAAAGCUAGGGUUAAUGGUUCUCUGUUCUAGGUUCUUCAUUUAAAAAAUGUAUUCAUUAAGAUAUGGUCCCAGCCGGACGUGGUGGCUCACACCUGUAAUCCCAGCACUUUGGGAGGCUCAGGUGGGCAGAUCACUUGAGGUCAGGAGUUUGAGACCAGCCUGGCCAAUACGGUGAAAACCCAUCUCU